AAGCUGCAGGCUCCCUGCCCAUAAAACAGGGUGUGAAAGGCAUCUCAGCGGCUGCCCCACCAUGGCUACCUGGGCCCUCCUGCUCCUUGCAGCCAUGCUCCUGGGCAACCCAGCCCCUGCCUCCGCAUCUGCGUGGUGAAGGCCAUUGGCCCUCAUCGGUGGAUCUGCGUUUCCUCGGGCCUACACUGUCUAGGAUUGUGCGGGGCUGGUGAGAGAACAAGAUCUCUUCUGUGUUCAAGGCAGACUUCCUGCCCCCUGCACCCUGCUCUCUCCCAGGCCUUGAGGUCAGUGUGAGCCCCAAGGGCAAGAACACUUCUGGAAGGGAGAGUGGAUUUGGCUGGGCCAUCUGGAUGGAAGGUCUGGUCUUCUCUCGUCUGAGCCCUGAGUACUACGACCUGGCAAGAGCCCACCUGCGUGAUGAGGAGAAAUCCUGCCCGUGCCUGGCCCAGGAGGGCCCCCAGGGUGACCUGUUGACCAAAACACAGGAGCUGGGCCGUGACUACAGGACCUGUCUGACGAUAGUCCAAAAACUGAAGAAGAUGGUGGAUAAGCCCACCCAGAGAAGUGUUUCCAAUGCUGCGACCCGGGUGUGUAGGACGGGGAGGUCACGAUGGCGCGACGUCUGCAGAAAUUUCAUGAGGAGGUAUCAGUCUAGAGUUACCCAGGGCCUCGUGGCCGGAGAAACUGCCCAGCAGAUCUGUGAGGACCUCAGGUUGUGUAUACCUUCUACAGGUCCCCUCUGAGCCCUCUCACCUUGUCCUGUGGAAGAAGCACAGGCUCCUGUCCUCAGAUCCCGGGAACCUCAGCAACCUCUGCCGGCUCCUCGCUUCCUCGAUCCAGAAUCCACUCUCCAGUCUCCCUCCCCUGACUCCCUCUGCUGUCCUCCCCUCUCACGAGAAUAAAGUGUCAAGCAAGAUUUUAGCCGCAGCUGCUUCUUCUUUGGUGGAUUUGAGGGGUGGGUGUCAGUGGCAUGCUGGGGUGAGCUGUGUAGUCCUUCAAUAAAUGUCUGUCGUGUGUCCCA